AUGGGACUUCAGCAUGGCGGUGUUUGCAGAUUUGGACCUGCGAGCGGGUUCUGACCUGAAGGCUCUGCGCGGACUUGUGGAGACAGCCGCUCACCUUGGCUAUUCAGUUGUUGCUAUCAAUCAUAUCGUUGACUUUAAGGAAAAGAAACAGGAAAUUGAAAAACCAGUAGCUGUUUCUGAACUCUUCACAACUUUGCCAAUUGUACAGGGAAAAUCAAGACCAAUUAAAAUUUUAACUAGAUUAACAAUUAUUGUCUCGGAUCCAUCUCACUGCAAUGUUUUGAGAGCAACUUCUUCAAGGGCCCGGCUCUAUGAUGUUGUUGCAGUUUUUCCAAAGACAGAAAAGCUUUUUCAUAUUGCUUGCACACAUUUAGAUGUGGAUUUAGUCUGCAUAACUGUAACAGAGAAACUACCAUUUUACUUCAAAAGACCUCCUAUUAAUGUGGCGAUUGACCGAGGCCUGGCUUUUGAACUUGUCUAUAGCCCUGCUAUCAAAGACUCCACAAUGAGAAGGUAUACAAUUUCCAGUGCCCUCAAUUUGAUGCAAAUCUGCAAAGGAAAGAAUGUAAUUAUAUCUAGUGCUGCAGAAAGGCCUUUAGAAAUAAGAGGGCCAUAUGACGUGGCAAAUCUAGGCUUGCUGUUUGGGCUCUCUGAAAGUGACGCCAAGGCUGCGGUGUCCACCAACUGCCGAGCAGCGCUUCUCCAUGGAGAAACUAGAAAAACUGCUUUUGGAAUUAUCUCUACAGUGAAGAAACCUCGGCCAUCAGAAGGAGAUGAAGAUUGUCUUCCAGCUUCCAAGAAAGCCAAGUGGUCUCACUCUGUCACCCAGGCUGGAGUGCAGUGGCACAAUCUCGGCUCACUGCAACCUUUGCCUCUUGGGCUCAAGCCAUCCUCCCACCUCAGCCUCCCAAGAACUAGAAUUCAACAAAGACAACUUUUGAUCUCUCAUCAGAGAGAUCAUACUCCCAAGAACAGGCUUUGACCCUUCUUUAAAAGAGGAUUGUCCUGGGCUGAUGAGAGUCACUUUACCUGAAGAUACCUGGGAAGUUUUGUCUCCUCUGAGGUUGGCCCAUGGCCAGUGACUGAUGCAGGACAUUACAGCCUGGCCCACUGGCCUCGGUGGUACAAUUUAUGCUCCUGAGCACCCCAUGGGAUUACGCUGUGUGUGGAUUUCUCCUGAAACCACAUAUUUGCCUCUUCUGCCCUGUUCUGUUUUUUCUCAUUCCCUUAUAGAGGACUCUCAGUAAGUCACUUACACAAGAAUCCUAAUUUGAAAUGCUGCUUCCAGGAGACCUGACUUAGAAAAUUGGACAAAUAAAGUUGAUUUUUUUAAAUGUCCAGUAACAUGAAGAUGCUGAACUUUCCUAGUCAUUUAGGGGGAAAUCACCACAAAUAUAUCUGGCUGAUCAGGUUGAAAGUUAAAAGAAAAAAAGAUUUAUAAAGUGGGUAUUUUCAAGAUGGUGUGGAGGGAGAUACAAUUUGAUGCAAGUCUUAUACUUUUGAUGUCAAUUUAUUCUUCAGAAAUAACUGGUUAAUUAUAAAGGGUGGAUGGAUAAGGAUAUUCACUGCAACAAUGUCUUAAAUGUGAAAAUGGAAACAACCUAAAUACCCAAUAAUAACAGGAUUAAAUAAUUCAUUGUACAUUAAAAGAAUACUGUCUAUAAAGAUGUCUAGAAUAAGUUGUUCAGUUGAAGUUGUAAAGCUAAAUACACAAUACCCAUAAUGUGCACAGAAAUAAUCAGAAUGUCAUGAAACCAGGAUUAUUGGUGAUGUGUUGCUUCCUUUGUUACUCAUUUCUGUAUUGGCAUAAUGAGUAUUGGGUGUUCAAGAGGAGGGGGAAGGAAGUAUGACAGAUGUUAUGGGGAAAAAGCAAAGUACAACAGGAAGACACCUUGGGGGAACUAAUAGAAUCUAAGGACUCAAGGAUGGCUUCCUGGAGGAAAUACAGCUAGAACAAAGGGGAGGAAUGAGAAGUGAUGUGAUGGCGUGGAGUGGGCUGUAGUGGGAAGAAGAGUCUUCCAGGGAGCUGGCACAGUAUGUGAAAACAGUAAAGCAAGUGCCUGGAUUUUUUAAGGAACUGAAAAUUUAGUUGAGUUGAAAUUUAGAGUUUGGCUAGGAAGGUUAUGAGAGAUAAGAAUAAAGAGUUAACAGCAGCCAGAUUUUAAGGAUUUUAUAAGACAUUUUUAGGAGUUUUUAUUUCAUCCUGAGAGAAAUGUGAAGCCAUCGAAGGGUUGAAAGAGGAGAGUGAGUUGAUCAGCAUUGCAUUUUAGAAAAAUCCCUCUAUCUGCAACUUGAAAAACAUUCUGGAGGUAAGCAAGCCUGGAGGCCAGGAGCCUAGGAGGGCUAUUUGAUCCAGAUGAGAAGUAAUGGUGACCUGAACUAGGGCAGAGGCACCUAGGAUUGGAAAACAUGGACAGAUCACAGCACUACUUAUGUAGUAUACUUGGUAAGACCUGGUUGUUUAAAAGAGAAGGAUGAGGGAAAGAAGGUCAAAAACAACUUCUAGGACUCUCCAUUGGCCAGUGUGGUGUGCCCUUCACUGAAGAGCAAACACAAAAUGAAAGAUUGUGGGCAAAGAGUUGAGUCAGUGAGAAGGCAAGGAGAGAACCUUAUAAAAAAAUUGACUAUGUGAUUAAAAACUUAAAAAUUUCCCCCAACGUGUUUAUCUUUUCCAUUAGCAGAAAUAACUAAGAGUUGUCUUAAUUCUAAUGGGAUUUAUUCCAUAUUGUCUCUCAUGCCCUCUACCUAGUUAUUAGUGCAAAUAUUUAUAUGUGGCAACAUAAAACUUUUUAACUCUUUAUUCUCUUCUCUCGUGUACCCUCCCAGCUCUUUAGGGGAGGUGGAUUUGAGGCAGAUACCAUAAAGAAAAGUUGGUCACAUGGUGGUAACACGUUGAAGUUAUGCCACAUGAGACAUCAGCACUGGCAAGAGAAAUGUCUGUGUUGUAGAUGUUUCACUUGGAAGAAAUUGAAGGACCCUGAGCCUUAAAAGUCUGACAAACUUAAGCCAGGACCCCUGUGGGGAAGGUAGAGGGGCCAACAAACAAGAUUGGGAGUCAGAGAGAUAACAAUGAAAUCCCCAAUGCCUGUGGGAGGUGGACUCCCUGGAUUAGUACUAGACAGAAAAGGUACAAAAAUAUUUCAAACCAUUCUCACAACUCUAUAUGUGUCUAUGACCAGAUAACUGGAAGACCUUCUGGUUAUGGACUAUGCGUAUACACUCUCCCAGAUAGUUAGAGGCAUAUCUAAGAGGUUAACAUAUAUGAUCUUAUCCAAAAUGGGUCUCUUGGUGCUAGUGUUUUACAUCAGACUUCACUGGCUUUCAUGUAUUUCCACAAGUGCCAAACAUUUCUCAUAUCCUUGCUGUAUUCCAUAGAGCAGUGUUCCUGCUACCUGGAACACUUGAUUCUUGAAUAACUCCUGUUUACCUUUCAGACAAACCCUAAAGGUUACCACCUCAAAGAAGUCUUUAUAGAAGCCUCAUCAUCUUAGACACUCUGUAUUGUUUCCUUCAUCGUAUUUACAACAGACAGAUACUGUGCACUUACUGCCUCACUUAACGACAGGGAUACGUUCUGAAAGGUGCAUCAUUAGGCGGUUUUGUUGUGUGAACAUCACAGAGUGUUACUUACACAAACCUAAAUGAUACAGCCUACUAAACACCUAGGCUAUAUGAGCAAUACAGCCUAUUGCUCUUAGGCUUCAAACUUGUACGACAUGUCACUGUACUGAAUACUGUAGGCAACUAUAACACAGUGGUAAGUAUAUUGUGUAUCUAAACAAACAUAGAAAAGGUAAUGCACUGUACUAUGAUGUUACAACAGCUAGGAUGUUGCUAUCAAUAGAAAUUUUUCAGCUUCAUUUUAUUUUUAUGGGACCACCUUUGUAUAUGUGGUUCAUUGUUGGCCGAAACACCAUUCUGUGGCACAUGACUAUGUAUUUAUUCCUCAUUAUUCCUUUAAUAUUCAUCUCUUCCAGGAGGGCAUGUCAUGGACAAUCUCUUUUUCUUACCACAGGUCUUAGGACCUGGCCUAGCACCUGGCCAAGAACUACUGGCAUACCUCCUUUUAUUGUGCUUCAAUUUAUUGUGCUUUGCAAAUACUGAAUUUUUUACAAGUUGAAGAUUUGUGGCACCUCUGUAACCAGCAAGUCUAUUGGUGCCAUUUUUUCAACAUCAUGUGCCUGUUUCCUGUCUCGCUCAUGUCACAUUUUGGUAAUUUUCACAAUAUUAAAAACUUUUUCAUUAUUAUUA